CCCUUUGUGCGUCACGGGUGGCGGGCGCGGGAAGGGGAUUUGGAUUGUUGCGCCUCUGCUCUGAAGAAAGUGCUGUCUGGCUCCAACUCCAGUUCUUUCCCCUGAGCAGCGCCUGGAACCUAACCCUUCCCACUCUGUCACCUUCUCGAUCCCGCCGGCGCUUUAGAGCCGCAGUCCAGUCUUGGAUCCUUCAGAGCCUCAGCCACUAGCUGCGAUGCAUGUGAUCAAGCGAGAUGGCCGCCAAGAACGAGUCAUGUUUGACAAAAUUACAUCUCGAAUCCAGAAGCUUUGUUAUGGACUCAAUAUGGAUUUUGUUGAUCCUGCUCAGAUCACCAUGAAAGUAAUCCAAGGCUUGUACAGUGGGGUCACCACAGUGGAACUAGAUACUUUGGCUGCUGAAACAGCUGCAACCUUGACUACUAAGCACCCUGACUAUGCUAUCCUGGCAGCCAGGAUCGCUGUCUCUAACUUGCACAAAGAAACAAAGAAAGUGUUCAGUGAUGUGAUGGAAGACCUCUAUAACUACAUAAAUCCACAUAAUGGCAAACACUCUCCCAUGGUGGCCAAGUCAACAUUGGAUAUUGUUCUGGCCAAUAAAGAUCGCCUGAAUUCUGCUAUUAUCUAUGACCGAGAUUUCUCUUACAAUUACUUCGGCUUUAAGACGCUAGAGCGGUCUUAUUUGUUGAAGAUCAAUGGAAAAGUGGCUGAAAGACCACAACAUAUGUUGAUGAGAGUAUCUGUUGGGAUCCACAAAGAAGACAUUGAUGCAGCAAUUGAAACAUAUAAUCUUCUUUCUGAGAGGUGGUUUACUCAUGCUUCGCCCACUCUCUUCAAUGCUGGUACCAACCGCCCACAACUUUCUAGCUGUUUUCUUCUGAGUAUGAAAGAUGACAGCAUUGAAGGCAUUUAUGACACUCUAAAGCAAUGUGCAUUGAUUUCUAAGUCUGCUGGAGGAAUUGGUGUUGCUGUGAGUUGUAUUCGGGCUACUGGCAGCUACAUUGCUGGGACUAAUGGCAAUUCCAAUGGCCUUGUACCGAUGCUGAGAGUAUAUAACAACACAGCUCGAUAUGUGGAUCAAGGUGGGAACAAGCGUCCUGGGGCAUUUGCUAUUUACCUGGAGCCUUGGCAUUUAGACAUCUUUGAAUUCCUUGAUUUAAAGAAGAACACAGGAAAGGAAGAGCAGCGUGCCAGAGAUCUUUUCUUUGCUCUUUGGAUUCCGGAUCUCUUCAUGAAACGAGUGGAGACUAAUCAGGACUGGUCUUUGAUGUGUCCAAAUGAGUGUCCUGGUCUGGAUGAGGUUUGGGGAGAGGAAUUUGAGAAACUAUAUGCAAGUUAUGAGAAACAAGGUCGUGUCCGCAAAGUUGUAAAAGCUCAGCAGCUUUGGUAUGCCAUCAUUGAGUCUCAGACGGAAACAGGCACCCCGUAUAUGCUCUACAAAGAUUCCUGUAAUCGAAAGAGCAACCAGCAGAACCUGGGAACCAUCAAAUGCAGCAACCUGUGCACAGAAAUAGUGGAGUACACCAGCAAAGAUGAGGUUGCUGUUUGUAAUUUGGCUUCCCUGGCCCUGAAUAUGUAUGUCACAUCAGAACACACAUACGACUUUAAGAAGUUGGCUGAAGUCACUAAAGUCGUUGUCCGAAACUUGAAUAAAAUUAUUGAUAUAAACUACUAUCCUGUACCAGAGGCAUGCCUAUCAAAUAAACGCCAUCGCCCCAUUGGAAUUGGGGUACAAGGUCUGGCAGAUGCUUUUAUCCUGAUGAGAUACCCUUUUGAGAGUGCAGAAGCCCAGUUACUGAAUAAGCAGAUCUUUGAAACUAUUUAUUAUGGUGCUCUGGAAGCCAGCUGUGACCUUGCCAAGGAGCAGGGCCCAUACGAAACCUAUGAGGGCUCUCCAGUUAGCAAAGGAAUUCUUCAGUAUGAUAUGUGGAAUGUUACUCCUACAGACCUAUGGGACUGGAAGGUUCUCAAGGAGAAGAUUGCAAAGUAUGGUAUAAGAAACAGUUUACUUAUUGCCCCGAUGCCUACAGCUUCCACUGCUCAGAUCCUGGGGAAUAAUGAGUCCAUUGAACCUUACACCAGCAACAUCUAUACUCGCAGAGUCUUGUCAGGAGAAUUUCAGAUUGUAAAUCCUCACUUAUUGAAAGAUCUUACCGAGCGGGGCCUAUGGCAUGAAGAGAUGAAAAACCAGAUUAUUGCAUGCAAUGGCUCUAUUCAGAGCAUACCAGAAAUUCCUGAUGACCUGAAGCAACUUUAUAAAACUGUGUGGGAAAUCUCUCAGAAAACUGUUCUCAAGAUGGCAGCUGAGAGAGGUGCUUUCAUUGAUCAAAGCCAAUCUUUGAACAUCCACAUUGCUGAGCCUAACUAUGGCAAACUCACUAGUAUGCACUUCUACGGCUGGAAGCAGGGUUUGAAGACUGGGAUGUAUUAUUUAAGGACAAGACCAGCGGCUAAUCCAAUCCAGUUCACUCUAAAUAAGGAGAAGCUAAAAGAUAAAGAAAAGGUAUCAAAAGAGGAAGAAGAGAAGGAGAGGAACACAGCAGCCAUGGUGUGCUCUUUGGAGAAUAGAGAUGAAUGUCUGAUGUGUGGAUCCUGAGGAAAGACUUGGAAGAGACCAGCAUGUCUUCAGUAGCCAAACUACUUCUUGAGCAUAGAUAGGUAUAGUGGGUUUGCUUGAGGUGGUAAGGCUUUGCUGGACCCUGUUGCAGGCAAAAGGAGUAAUUGAUUUAAAGUACUGUUAAUGAUGAUAAUGAUUUUUUUUUUAAACUCAUAUAUUGGGAUUUUCACCAAAAUAAUGCUUUUGAAAAAAAGAAAAAAAAAACGGAUAUAUUGAGAAUCAAAGUAGAAGUUUUAGGAAUGCAAAAUAAGUCAUCUUGCAUACAGGGAGUGGUUAAGUAAGGUUUCAUCACCCCUUUAGCACUGCUUUUCUGAAGACUUCAGUUUUGUUAAGGAGAUUUAGUUUUACUGCUUUGACUGGUGGGUCUCUAGAAGCAAAACUGAGUGAUAACUCAUGAGAAGUACUGAUAGGACCUUUAUCUGGAUAUGGUCCUAUAGGUUAUUCUGAAAUAAAGAUAAACAUUUCUAAGUGAUUGUAUGAGAUUAAUUUUGUCAUUUACUUUCAUAUAAAAGUCAAAUUUGAAAAACA